AUUCAUCCCGCAUCCUGCUGGGAAACAGCGUCCAUCCGACACAGCACCGCCCACAGCGGGCCCUCGGCGUGGCCCGCAGGCCCUUCGGACCGCCUGGGAGCGCGGCCACACGUGCCAGCAAGUGAGGGCAGCGACCUGGGACCGCCGCGUCUACUUACACCGCGACGACUCCGCGAUCCACGGACACCGCCCGGCCCCCACGGCGGCCCUGCAGGGGAGAACUCGGGCCGCCUUCCCGAGUCCCGGCCGCCGCUGUUCGGCUCGCGCGGCUGCCCGCCGGGGACCCGAACGGAAGAAGGGUGGCGAGGCGGGAAAGGAAAAGGCCUGAGGGUCCAAGGCAGGAGGGGACACACGGAACACGCCGAGGGCCAACCACGCCGCCGCGCGCUCCCCGGCUAGGACCCACCUGCUGCAGACAGACCUCGGCUGCCCGACAACUACACGCAGGACACGUGGCGGAAGCUGCACGAGGCGGUGCGGGCCGUGCAGAGCAGCACCUCCAUCAGGUACAACCUCGAGGAGCUCUACCAGGCUGUGGAAAAUCUCUGUUCUCACAAAGUCUCCCCAAUGCUCUACAAGCAACUGCGUCAGGCCUGUGAAGACCACGUCCAGGCACAGAUCCUUCCGUUUAGAGAAGACUCACUAGAUAGUGUUUUAUUUUUAAAGAAGAUUAACACGUGCUGGCAGGACCACUGCAGACAAAUGAUCAUGAUCAGAAGCAUCUUCCUGUUCUUGGACCGCACCUAUGUGCUGCAGAACUCCACGCUGCCCUCCAUCUGGGAUAUGGGAUUAGAACUGUUUAGAACCCAUAUUAUUAGUGAUAAAAUGGUUCAGAGUAAAACCAUUGAUGGAAUCCUACUGCUGAUCGAGCGCGAGAGGAGCGGCGAGGCCGUGGACCGGAGCCUGUUGCGGAGCCUCCUGGGCAUGCUGUCUGACCUGCAGGUGUAUAAAGAUUCAUUUGAACUGAAAUUUUUGGAAGAGACUAAUUGCUUAUAUGCUGCCGAAGGCCAAAGGUUAAUGCAGGAAAGAGAGGUUCCAGAAUAUCUUAACCAUGUAAGUAAACGCUUAGAGGAAGAGGGAGACAGAGUAAUCACUUACUUGGACCACAGCACACAGAAACCACUGAUUGCUUGUGUGGAGAAACAGCUAUUAGGAGAACAUUUAACAGCAAUUCUGCAGAAAGGGCUCGACCACUUACUGGAUGAGAACAGAGUGCCGGACCUCGCACAGAUGUACCAGCUGUUCAGCCGGGUGAGGGGCGGGCAGCAGGCGCUGCUGCAGCACUGGAGCGAGUACAUCAAGACUUUUGGAACAGCGAUCGUAAUCAAUCCUGAGAAAGACAAAGACAUGGUCCAAGACCUGUUGGACUUCAAGGACAAGGUGGACCACGUGAUCGAGGUCUGCUUCCAGAAGAAUGAGCGGUUCGUCAACCUGAUGAAGGAGUCCUUUGAGACGUUCAUCAACAAGAGACCCAACAAGCCUGCAGAACUGAUCGCAAAGCAUGUGGAUUCAAAGUUAAGAGCAGGCAACAAAGAAGCCACAGACGAGGAGCUGGAGCGGACGUUGGACAAGAUCAUGAUCCUGUUCAGGUUUAUCCACGGUAAAGAUGUCUUUGAAGCAUUUUAUAAAAAAGAUUUGGCAAAAAGACUCCUUGUUGGGAAAAGUGCCUCAGUCGAUGCUGAAAAGUCUAUGUUGUCAAAGCUCAAGCAUGAGUGCGGUGCAGCCUUCACCAGCAAGCUGGAAGGCAUGUUCAAGGACAUGGAGCUUUCGAAGGACAUCAUGGUUCAUUUCAAGCAGCAUAUGCAGAAUCAGAGUGACUCAGGCCCUAUAGACCUCACAGUGAACAUACUCACAAUGGGCUACUGGCCAACAUACACGCCCAUGGAAGUGCACUUAACCCCAGAAAUGAUUAAACUUCAGGAAGUAUUUAAGGCAUUUUAUCUUGGAAAGCACAGUGGUCGAAAACUUCAGUGGCAAACUACUUUGGGACAUGCUGUUUUAAAAGCGGAGUUUAAAGAAGGGAAGAAGGAAUUCCAGGUGUCCCUCUUCCAGACACUGGUGCUCCUCAUGUUCAACGAGGGAGAUGGCUUCAGCUUUGAGGAGAUAAAAAUGGCCACGGGGAUAGAGGAUAGUGAAUUGCGCAGAACGCUGCAGUCCCUGGCCUGUGGCAAAGCACGUGUGCUGAUUAAAAGUCCCAAAGGAAAGGAAGUGGAAGAUGGAGACAAGUUCAUUUUUAAUGGAGAGUUCAAGCACAAGUUGUUUAGAAUAAAGAUCAAUCAAAUUCAGAUGAAGGAAACUGUUGAGGAACAGGUUAGCACCACUGAGAGAGUGUUUCAGGAUAGACAAUAUCAGAUUGAUGCUGCUAUCGUCAGAAUAAUGAAGAUGAGAAAGACUCUUGGUCAUAAUCUUCUAGUUUCUGAAUUAUAUAAUCAGCUGAAAUUUCCAGUAAAGCCUGGAGAUUUGAAAAAGAGAAUUGAAUCUCUGAUAGACAGAGACUAUAUGGAGAGAGACAAAGACAAUCCGAAUCAGUACCACUACGUGGCCUGACGCAUCUGCAGACGGUUCCCCUUCAUGAAACACUAGAAUGUACCCUCAGAGCAGGAAGCACACCUGUGCCAUUUCUGGGACUCUGAUUGAUCCAGCUGUGGACAUUGGAAGGCGAAGGAAGGGAGGUGGCUCCUGGGUCAUCUUUCACAAGGCUCAAGACUUCAACCUGCAGAUGUAUCUUUUUCCCUCCAGUUUUUCCUCUAGUUCUUUUAGGCAUUUAAAUUGUUUCUGUUACUCUGUGCAAAAUAACUUUGAGAUUGGACAAGAAGAUGUUACUAAAGAGAAGUUCCUUUAAAAGGUCUUGUUCUUGUGUCAAAAAGCUGCAAGUUUGGUUUGUUCUCGUGUGUGAUCAUGAGUGCACAAUGAAGAAGACCCUAGAUGCUGCAUUUUUUAGCUCUGAAGAUUCCUUAGGUAUCCCUGAAGACAGCUCGCUCAGAUGAUCAGCAUUUAGAGUGAAAACAAGGGCCCUUCAUGGGUGAACAUUAGAAAGAGCCAGGGUUCAAAGCUGGCGAAUGGAUGACGCACCCUAGCCACUGGCCCCUCUCUGUUUCAUGUAUUUCCAAAAGUUGUAAACUUUGAUGGCUGAUUUUUCGUAAGUCAGGUUUCUAAGUGAGCUCCCUGAGGUGCCAAGGCCAUGGUGUCCGCCCUGCUGCGUCUGUUCGUCAGCUGAGUUCCUUGUGAAUCUCUGUUUUAGGGUUUGGGGCUAGUGUGUUUGUGUUUCCAUUCUAAGAUUGAGUCUGGCAGUCCCUGUUUUUUUGCAUUGGGGUAACUGCUCUUUGAUUUUUUUUAAUUGCAGUAUUUGUGUGAUUGCAAUAAUAAAGUUUGGUUUGGUUUUUACAGUCAUGCGCAGGGACGAUCCUUGUUCUCUGCUGUAAACUGUAAAAAGUUUAUGGAGACUUAAAGUCUUGAUGUUGUGAAGCAGAGGUUAUUUUGUGGAAAGAUUAAAAGGAUUUUGUUGGUACCUGGUUUUGUGUUGUGUAUAUAUACAUGAGGUUGAACAGUGAAAGGAAAGUUCAGUAGUGAUGUUAGAAGGGUAACUAUGACAAAGAUACUUUUGAGAUAACAUUUAAAAGUACUUUAUAUUUUACAUAAUAGCAUGUUUCAUUUUGAUUAAAAGCUACCAAAGGAAUUUUGAUCAUGGCAUAAGUGUUUAAAGCAAUAUUUUCUGGAAUAUACCAAGUUUAUAUAAUUUGAUUUUGUGCUAAAUUAUUAAGAGUCUCUUUUUGAAACAUGCGGGUUUGAAAUAUGACACCUUGUGGGUUUCCAUAUUAAAAUCCUCACUCUUUAAUUGUCAUUUCUAUCUUUGAAAAUUUUCAUUUAUGAGUUCCAUGAUAUGUGGUCUAAGAAAGACCAAACAGAUUUCUAUUUUUUUUUUCUUAUAAGUUCGUUGUGUCUAGAGAUUGUUAAUAUUGUAAUUUAAUGUAGACUUACUUUGAAUAAAAUUAGUUUAAUUGGCCUUAAAAUUACAUUAAUAAAACUUUGUGAUAUGCAAAUGACACAUUCUUCAUAACUCUUUAGCAGCUUUGACUACUAGUGCACUAGACAGAAGUCAGAGCAGGGAGCACCUGUCCCCUCUCAAGUGAUUAUUCUUUCCUGGCCACCUCUACCACAAAAUACCAGUGGGGCCAGGUAGUGACAAGUGGGUCUUUUUUACUUGGACGAUUCGUUGUGCUGUGCCUUUGUUUCAUUUGAGCACAGUGGCUCACGCCUGUAGUCCCAGCUAUGGGAGGGCAAGGUGGGAGGAUCGUUUGAGCCUGAGUUCCAGACCAUCCUGAGCACCAUAGGGAGAUCCUGUUUCCAUUUUAGUUUAUUUAUUUUUAAUUGAGGUGGAGUCUUGCUCUGUUGCCCAAGCUGGAGUGCAGUGGUGCAAUCUCAGCUCACUGCACCCUCCGCCUCCUGGGUUCAAGCAGUUCUCCCACCUCAGUCUCCCAAGUAGCUGGGAUUACAGGCACCCGCCAUCAUGCCCAGCUAAUAUUUGUAUUUUUGUAGAGACGGGGUUUCACUAUGUUGGCCAGACUGGUCUUGAACUCCUAACCUCAGGUGAUCUGCCCGCCUUGGCCUCCCAAAGUGCUGGGAUUACAGGCGUGAGCCACCAUGCCCGGCCUGCCUGUUUCUGUUUUAUAAAAGAAAGGAAAAUCUAUUUAUAUCUAUUCUCUUAUUUAGCAAUAUUUAAUGUUUUAUUGUUAAAGGUCAGUGUGGUAAAACAAAUAGUAUAGAAGAAAUCAUUGAAAAAGAAACAGCACUUAGACAGAAAUGCUGUAAAAGUGGAAAGGAGAAGGUGAAAUUACUUGCAGGUUAGAUGGUUGCAUACCCAGGUCAUCUAAGGAGCAAAUGAAAAUCUGUGACUGAAGAAAGAAUUCACCAAGUUAACCAGACACAAAAUUAACAAAAACAUCAGUAGCUUUCCUAUAAAUAUAGGCUAUAAUGGAGGGUCAUUUUUUAUUUUUAUUUAGAGACAGGGUCUUAACUGUCACCUGGACUGGAGUGCAGUGGCAUGAUCAUGUUUCACGGCAGCCUCUACCUUCUGGGCUCAAGCGAUCCUCUCUUCUCAGCCACCUGAGUAGCUGGGCCUACAGGUGUACAUCACCACGCCCAGAUAAUUUUUAUUGUAUUUUUUAUAGAGGCAGUGUCUUGCUAUGUUGCCAAGGCUGUUCUUGUACUCCUGGCCUCAAGCGAACCUCCUACCUCAGCCUCCCCAAAUGCUGGGAUUACAGGCAUGAGACACUGCACCUGACCAGAAGUCAUUUUUUCAAUAGCAACCCCCAAAAAAGAUAAAAUACCUAGUAACAAAUAGGGAAACACCUAUGUGAAAGGUAUUAUAACAUUACUAAGGAACACAGGCCCUGAAUAAGUGAAAGUUCUGUUGAUUCUCACAUUUUGCUAUACAGUAUCUUAAGAUGUAAAACCUUCCUUUAAAACACAAGCGGAUUCUAAAGUUAAAACAGAAAAGCAAAUAUGCCAGACUAGUCAAAUUGUUUUAAAUUCUGCUGUUUUUAGAACAUUGUAAUUGAAACAGCAUGAUGCUGGCCCUUUAAAAAGAUUCCUGGAACAAGAAAGUCCACAAAUAAGCCAAAUACACAGGAACUCGGCGUGGCACAAAGGGGCCGUGUGUGAUCAGGAACUGGAACUUUGCAACAACUACCCAUGCUCAGAAGUUUGGGCCACCUUGAAAAGAGAAAAGUUGGAUUAGACUCCUUUUUAUACUAAGGGAAGUUCCAAGUGGUCAAGUAUUUACGUGUAAAAAAAUACAUAUAUAUGAAACCAUAAUCAUAAGAUACUUUUUUUGUAAAUUGACUAUUAUUGUAUAAAUUUAUAGAGUAUAAAGUGAUCUUAUAAAUUAUGCAUACAUUGUGGACUAGUCAAGCUAGUUACAUCCAUCACCUCAAAUACUUAACAUUUUUGUAGUGAGAACAUCUGAAAUUUACUCUUAGCAAUUUUGAAAUGUACAAUACUCAAUUUUUGACUGUAUUCACCAUGCUGUACAAUAGAACUCAGAAAAAGAAAAAUAUAGUCCUCCUUUCUAAGA